AGGCUCUGGAGGGACCCAGGAGCUGCCGCCGGCCUCAGCCCAUGGCCCGGAGGGUAGGUCUCGGGGCGGGGACCCCGCGUCCCGGCCGCUUCCGCACCCCCUGUCCCUGCAUCCCCCACUCUCCGGCGCUGGCCCCCAUUAGCCCAUCCGUCCUCUACACCACCUCGCUCUCUCUCUGCCCCUCCCUCCGCCCCUGGGUCUCCCAGUCCCUGUGUGCCCCCUCUCUGCCCCCAAGUGUCUCUUCCUGGCCCUCGGCCUCGCCUCCUCCCCAUCGUUUAGCUUCUCCUUCUCCCUGCCCCUCUGUCCCCCUCUGUCUGCCCCACUCUCCUCCUCCUUUCUGCCUCUCUGUCCCCCUCUCUCUGUCCCUGGUCUCCCCCCUCUUUCUGCCUCUCUAUCCCCCUCUCUCUGCCCUCCCCCACCCGCAGUCUCUCUCCUCUGUUCCUGGGCUUCCUCCUCCAUCUCAGCCGCCCGCACCUCACCGUCCCCCCUUUUUUCUGCUCUCCUCCGUCCUUCCCUUCGCUCUACUUUUGUUCCAAGCCGCCCCUGCCUCUCCAGGGCUAGGAGUGGGACAGGGGUGGGAGAGGUGGUCUCACCAGGCUGCUGGCCCCACGGAGCCUGUCUCCCUGGGGAUGGGAACGGGGAUAGAAGACAGGGGAGGAGGCGCGCGCCCGUUUUGGGGGUUCCGGGUAGGCUGUGAGGACCGCUUUUGGUGAGAGUGCCUUGAGCAGCGGGGAGCAGUUGGAUUCAACUUCAGGGCACAGGAGAAGUUAGGAGAAGAGGGAGAGGGAAAGAGUGGGACACACAGAACCAGGGUGCCCAGCCAGGCGAGGGUCCGAGGCAGGAACGUUCUAGCCUCUUCCCGUGCGAGUCCUGCUGCCUCUUUGAGCCUCCGUGUCUUCAUCACUGAGGAAGGGAUUUGACCUGAUGAGAGGAAGGUGCCCCUGGCUUCCCAGGUGCAUGGUUCUGUGACGACAGGACGCGGUCGUCCUACCCCAUAAUGGUGUUUCUCUUGGGUGCGCAAUCGUGUCUGUAUGGUGGUGCGGAGUGACCCUCUCCGGCAACAAGUGCUCACAGCAUGAGCCAGGCCCUGUGCUAAAUGCCUCAUUCAUUCAUUCAUCCAUGUGCCAAAUGUCUCAAUCAUGCAUUCAUUCUUGUGCCUGGUGUUGGGCUGUGUGCAUGUGUGUGUGCAUGUGUGUGUGGGGGGGGGGAUUUGGGUGUGACUGACACAUGAGUGUGCACGUGGGUUGGUGUGUAUGGCUGUGUCUACAUGUGUGGUAGAUUCACGUGGCGAGUGGAGUGUGACAUGUUGUUGAGACUUACUCUGAUGCGCUUAUCUGCCAACUGUGAAAUGAAAUAGAAGACAGGGAGGCUUCGUAUGUGUACUUUGUGUACAACAAUGCGCGGUUCCUACAGGAGGUGUCCAUGGAUCUCCCUCUCUGUCUGUCUCUCUCUCUGUCUCUGUCACUGUCUUCUCACGCCACUUUCUCCAUCUCUUUUCCCUCCCAGCCAGACCCUGCCGUCUCUCCCUCUGGGUCCUCCUGCCCACAUGUCAGGAAUCUCUGCCUGGACGGGGUCCUCACUCCCCACCGAGGCAGCUCCAGGGGACCUGGAGGGCUUCAAGCUUGGGGGCUCAGACACCUGGGGACCACAGUAUGAUGAGCUGCCGCACUACCCAGGCAUCGUGGAUGGCCCCGCAGCCCUGGCUAGCUUCCCAGAGACAGUGCCCGCAGUACCAGGGCCCUAUGGCCCGCACCGGCCUCCCCAGCCCCUGCCCCCAGGCUUGGACAGCGACGGCCUGAAGAGGGAGAAGGAUGAGAUCUAUGGACACCCGCUCUUCCCCCUCUUGGCCCUGGUCUUUGAGAAAUGUGAACUGGCUACAUGCUCUCCCCGUGACGGGGCCGGAGCUGGGCUGGGGACACCCCCUGGAGGUGACGUCUGCUCCUCUGAUUCCUUCAACGAGGACAUCGCUGCCUUUGCCAAGCAGGUUCGCUCUGAGAGGCCCCUCUUCUCCUCCAACCCAGAACUGGACAAUCUGAUGAUCCAGGCCAUCCAGGUGCUGCGGUUCCACCUGCUGGAGCUGGAGAAGGUCCACGACCUGUGCGACAACUUCUGUCACCGCUACAUCACCUGCCUCAAGGGAAAGAUGCCCAUCGACCUGGUCAUCGAGGAUCGGGACGGCGGCUGCAGGGAGGACUUCGAGGACUACCCAGCCUCCUGCCCCAGCCUCCCAGACCAGAAUAAUAUGUGGAUUCGAGACCAUGAGGAUAGUGGGUCUGUACAUUUGGGGACCCCAGGUCCAUCCAGUGGGGGCCUGGCCUCCCAGAGUGGGGACAACUCCAGUGACCAAGGAGACGGGCUGGACACCAGCGUGGCCUCUCCCAGUUCUGGUGGAGAAGAUGAGGACUUGGACCAGGAGCGACGGCGAAACAAGAAGAGGGGGAUCUUCCCCAAGGUGGCCACCAACAUCAUGCGAGCCUGGUUGUUCCAGCACCUCUCGCACCCGUACCCCUCGGAGGAGCAGAAGAAACAGCUGGCGCAGGACACGGGGCUCACCAUCCUGCAAGUCAACAACUGGUUCAUUAACGCCCGGAGACGCAUCGUGCAACCUAUGAUCGAUCAAUCCAACCGCACAGGGCAGGGUGCAGCCUUCAGCCCAGAGGGCCAGCCCAUCGGGGGCUAUACCGAGACGCAGCCACACGUGGCCGUCCGGCCUCCGGGAUCAGUGGGGAUGAGUUUGAACUUGGAAGGAGAAUGGCAUUAUCUAUAGAGGCUGAUGCAGGAGAGACCCAGCCUCCGGCUGUGACCCCCAGCCUCACACCUGCCUCUGGUUCCCGCCUGGUCCUCCAGCUUCAGGACCCCACCUCCAAAGGCCCCUCUGCUCAAUGCCUACCUCCCUAGGGCCCUGCUGGGACAUGGGGGCCUGAGUGCCCAUCCAAGGGCUCUCAAGGACACCGGCAAGGCCUCCAGGCCCUGAGCCCCACUUCUGCCUUCACCUCUGCCUGGGACCCGAGCUGGGCUCCUGGGCCUUGGUCCCCAGAAGAUGGCGGCUAGGGCCUCGCCGCCAGGACAGAGAAGGGACGGGGUGGCUGGGCAGUCAGGGAAGGAGGGUCGCCCGGAUCCGACAUUUUGGAGAGAUUCCUUCACUCUCCUGUCCCCCCUACCUCCCUUCUCUAAUUUCUUCUUUUUUUUAAUGAUAAAGUCUUAAAAACACGGA